GCAGUCCGACGCCGACUGAGGCACGAGCGGGUGACGCUGGGCCUGCAGCGCGGAGCAGAAAGCAGAACCCGCAGGUGAGCAAGGGGGCAGCGGGCCGGGGUAGCCUGCCGGACAACCAUAGGCAAAGUUAGUUUUAGCCCCCGCUUCUGCGGUCCGGCUCGGACAACUUUCCUCGGAACUAGUGACAGGUCGGGGCAGCUGGUGGGUGAAAAGGAGCUUUAGCCACCAGUCCUGAACCCCCAGUUCUCACACUCGGCCGUGCACAGCUGCGUGAUCCUGGGUCCGUCCCUCUACCUGGCUCUGGACCUCCCGGGUUCCAGCAGGAGGAAGUGAACCAGGUGAAUUCCACGCUCCCGUUGCCCUUUCUCACUUAAAACGCCGGAAGGUGAGAGCUGGCAGGUGAGAGCAGGCUGCAGGUCGCCACAGGUGUUCCCAUCGCGUUGCCCUCUGCAGUUUCUCUCCCUGCAAAAUGGGACUGAGAGAAGCGAAUUGCUUUAAAGAGUGCACUGUUUCCUCGGUUGGGGCUCGAACCCACCAACCCUGGGGAAGAGGAGGCCAAAGCAGGGAGGUUCCAUUUCCCGCCUCACCUGCUUCCCACCAAUUCUAACAGUUCAACUGAGCCGGACCCCCUAAGACUUCAAGUUGGAAACUCAGUGGGGCUUUUCCAGAGUCCUCCCUGCUGCUGUGUGGACGACACGUGGGCACAGGCAGAAGUGGGCCCUGUGACCAGCUGCACUGGUUUCGUGGAAGGAAGCUCCAGGACUGGCGGGAUGGGCUCAGCCUGUAUCAAAGUCACCAAAUACUUUCUCUUCCUCUUCAACUUGAUCUUCUUUAUCCUGGGCGCAGUGAUCCUGGGCUUCGGGGUGUGGAUCCUGGCCGACAAGAGCAGUUUCAUCUCUGUCCUGCAAACCUCCUCCAGCUCGCUUAGGAUGGGGGCCUAUGUCUUCAUCGGCGUGGGGGCAGUCACUAUGCUCAUGGGCUUCCUGGGCUGCAUCGGCGCCGUCAACGAGGUCCGCUGCCUGCUGGGGCUGUACUUUGCUUUCCUGCUCCUGAUCCUCAUUGCCCAGGUGACGGCCGGGGCCCUCUUCUACUUCAACAUGGGCAAGCUGAAGCAGGAGAUGGGCGGCAUCGUGACUGAGCUCAUUCGAGACUACAACAGCAGUCGCGAGGACAGCCUGCAGGAUGCCUGGGACUACGUGCAGGCUCAGGUGAAGUGCUGCGGCUGGGUCAGCUUCUACAACUGGACAGACAACGCUGAGCUCAUGAAUCGCCCUGAGGUCACCUACCCCUGUUCCUGCGAAGUCAAGGGGGAAGAGGACAACAGCCUUUCUGUGAGGAAGGGCUUCUGCGAGGCCCCCGGCAACAGGACCCAGAGUGGCAACCACCCUGAGGACUGGCCUGUGUACCAGGAGGGCUGCAUGGAGAAGGUGCAGGCGUGGCUGCAGGAGAACCUGGGCAUCAUCCUCGGCGUGGGCGUGGGUGUGGCCAUCAUCGAGCUCCUGGGGAUGGUCCUGUCCAUCUGCUUGUGCCGGCACGUCCAUUCCGAAGACUACAGCAAGGUCCCCAAGUACUGAGGCAGCUGCUAUCCCCAUCUCCCUGCCUGGCCCCCAACCUCAGGGCUCCCAGGGGUCUCCCUGGCUCCCUCCUCCAGGCCUGCCUCCCACUUCACUGCGAAGACCCUCUUGCCCAUCCUGACUGAAAGUAGGGGGCUUUCUGGGGCCUAGCGAUCUCUCCUGGCCUAUCCGCUGCCAGCCUUGAGCCCUGGCUGUUCUGUGGUUCCUCUGCUCACCGCCCAUCAGGGUUCUCUUAGCAACUCAGAGAAAAAUGCUCCCCACAGCGUCCCUGGCGCAGGUGGGCUGGACUUCUACCUGCCCUCAAGGGUGUGUAUAUUGUAUAGGGGCAACUGUAUGAAAAAUUGGGGAGGAGGGGGCCGGGCGCGGUGGCUCACGCCUGUAAUCCCAGCACUUUGGGAGGCCGAGGCGGGUGGAUCACGAGGUCAGGAGAUCGAGACCAUCCUGGCUAACAUGGUGAAACCCCGUCUCUACUAAAAAUACAAAAAAAAUUUAGCCGGGCGCGGUGGCGGGCACCUGUAGUCCCAGCUACUUGGGAGGCUGAGGCAGGAGAAUGGUGUGAACCCGGGAGCGGAGGUUGCAGUGAGCUGAGAUCGUGCUACUGCACUCCAGCCUGGGGGACAGAAAGAGACUCCGUCUCAAAAAAAAAAAAAAAAAAAAAAAAAAUUGGGGAGGGAAGGGCGUUAGAUAAGGCACUCUGGGCUGUCAGGAGACUGCCUACUGGGUGGGUCAACUUAUUUCCCACUAUGACAUUUAUAUCUUUAUUUUUCACAAUUAUAUUGAAGGCAGUGGGAGAGGGGAGAGGGUGGGUUUUACCUGAUAUUAAGGGGUGGCACCCCUUCCCCAGGCCUGAUGCAGGUCCAUCUAGACAGCUCAGAUUAGCCUAGGCCAUGCCCUAGGGACACGGCCUAGGGGAGCUGGGCUGGAGGGGGUCUGCCUGGGUAAGGGGAUCUGGCUUGGCCCUGAGCUGCUUAGGGACAGGUGAGUCCUUGGGGGCAUGGCACAGAGCUGGUCCUGUAUUCUCCAGGGUCCGGAGCUGGCCAGGGGCGGGGAGGAGGAGGAUGGCUUCUCCUGGGAGAAGGUGGGCUGGCCUUUCUUGGCAAGCGGUCCUCUGGCCCCUGGGGAGUGGGGUGGGUGAGGCUGUGCCUUGUAGGGGGAGAGGGGAGGGGGCUUUGUGUGCACCAUUCUGUAAAACACACUCAAGAUUCUAAGACUAUUAAAGAGGAUUUAUAACA